GCGCAUCCUGAGAGAGACUGGAGAACUGGUGUCCGAGAGGCCCCGCCAACACCUGUGUGAUCAGUGGUUGCAGAGGCCAACAUCGCCAUGGGCUUUCAGGGCAGCUGGCGGACUCAGGGGCAUCUGAAGCAAAUUGAAACUGAUGGAGAAACACAGUGUCAGACACUACCUUGAAAAAAAUCAUCUUUCCCCGCGACCCUAAAGGUGUCCAUGUCUCAGUGACAAGGGAUGGCAGGUUGAUGGGUUUUGUUGACACUCUUCAUAACGAACUCUUCCCAAAACCACACGGCCUCGCACUUGGGAACUGAAACAUUUGUCCCGGAUGUUACAGGUCAGAGCCCUCCAGACCCCCAAGGACUGUACUCACUGCCCAGAAAUAGCUGCUGCCUCUGGGCAACCUUGUAGGCACCUUCUCCACCCAGGACAUGGGCACCCGUGACGAUGUCCCCGAAGCCAAGGUCCUGGUCCCCGUGGCCGUGUACUGCGGGAGCAUCCCUCGGACCAGUGCUGGGCCCCGGGUGCUCCCGCCUGGAAGCAUCAACUCCAGUCUGCCUCAUGGAGAAGGUUCUCUCCAGCCUGAGCCAAGAGCCCUGCUGAACAACGAGGAACCGUCACAGCUCCUGCGUGGACUCGGACAGCUGGGUGGCCUCAAGCUGGACACCCCUUCCAAGGGCUGGCAGGCAAGGAAUGGUCACCCCAGGAACCUCAGGGCCUUGUCUUUGGGGGACCAGCCCCUGGUGCUCCUCCCUUCUCCGGAGUCAGAGGCCAACAGCGUGGCCAGGGACACCAUCCAGAUUAAGGACAAGCUCAAGAAAAGGAGGCUCUCAGAGGGCUUGGCAGCGUCUUCCCGAGCCUCUCUGGAUCCAGGGGGAGGCCCCCAAGGAGUUCCCCUGCACAGCACCAUCCCCCGAGCCACCUCUCAGAGGCUGCUGAGGGUGCCCAGGCCGAUGCCUCUCAUCCAGAGCAUCCCUACCACCCCUGAGGCCAGCGGAGUCAAAGAGAAGGGCCUGGACCUACCGGGGAGCAUUCCGGGUCCUCACGAGUUGAGACCCGGUGCUCAGGAGGCGCAGAUCUCCUGGCAAUACCUGCACUGCAAUGAUGAGAAGAUGCAGAAGUCCCUGGGCGCCAUCGUGAUCCCACCCAUCCCAAAGGCCAGGACGGUUGCAGCGACCCCCUCCCGUGUGCCUGGCUCCCUUCCCAGCCCGUUACCUCCAGGCCAGGGAGUCCUCACAGGCCUGAGGGCCCCACGCACGCGAUUGGCUCGGGGGAGUGGGCCUCGGGAGAAGACCCCUGCAUCUCUGGAGCCAAAACCUUUGGCCUCACCCAUCAGAGACAGGCCUGCCGCUGCCAAGAAGCCUGCCCUGCCUUUUUCUCAGUCUGCUCCCACGCUGACAGCCUUCUCCUUUGACUGUGCCAGAGAAGCCUGCCCUCCGCUGAAAGAAGAGGACCAGAAGGAGAUCGGCACCAAGAUCCAAGUCACCAUCUCCAAGUCUGCCCGGGAGAAGAUGCAGCUGAAGCAGAUGAAGGAGAUGGAGCUGCUUCGGAGGCUGGAGGAGCCCAGGACAGGGCAGGAGCUCACUUCCCAGUGCCUGGGCUCCCAGAGAGCCUUCAUGAAGGAAGGCCUCCUUCCCCUCCGGGGCAGCGGGACACUGUCUGUGCCCACUAGGCUGAGCGGCCCAUGCAGAAACGACGUCAGCAUCAUCCUGAGGAAGUGGGCCAGCCGGGCCUCCCUGCCCAGCAUCCCCAUCAGCCGGCAGGAGCCCCGCUUUGCCCGCCACGCCUCAGCUAACUCAUUACCUGCGGUGCUCACGUUGGGGUCUCCUGAAUGGGAAGAAGAGGAGGAGAUGGAUCUUAGAGCCUGUAAGGAGUUGAGGCCUUUCUCGAACCCGGAGCUGGGGCUGAGGGAUGCACUCCAGUGCCUCAACAGCAGUGACUGGCAGAUGAAGGAGAAGGGUCUGGUGAGCAUCCAGCGCUUGGCAGCCUGUCACUCAGAGGUCCUCACCGGGAAGCUGCACGACGUGUGCUUGGUGGUGACUGGGGAGGUCACCAACCUGCGGUCCAAGGUGUCUCACCUGGCCAUCAGCACCUUGGGAGACCUCUUCCAGGCCUUGAAGAAGAAUAUGGACCAGGAGGCCGAGGAGAUCGCCCGCUGCUUGCUGCAGAAGAUGGCGGACACCAACGAGUUCAUCCAGAGAGCAGCCGGCCAGUCUCUGAGGGCUAUGGUGGAGAAUGUGACCCUUGCCCGCUCCCUGGUGGUCCUCACCUCGGCGGGUGUCUACCACCGGAACCCCUUGAUCCGGAAAUACGCGGCUGAGCACCUCUCAGCUGUGCUGGAGCAGAUCGGCGCUGAGAAGCUUCUCUCGGGCACCAGAGACAGCACAGACAUGUUGGUGCACAACCUGGUGAGGCUGGCACAGGACUCCAACCAGGACACCAGAUUUUAUGGCCGGAAGAUGGUGAAUAUCUUGAUGGCGAACACUAAGUUUGAUGCAUUUCUGAAGCAAUCUCUCCCAUCUUACGACUUGCAGAAGGUCAUGGCGGCCAUUAAACAGCAGGGAAUAGAAGAUAAUGAUGAACUUCCCUCUGCCAAAGGCCGCAAGGUGUUGAGGAGUCUGGUGGUGUGUGAGAACGGGCUGCCCAUCAAGGAGGGGCUCAGCUGCAAUGGCCCAAGGCUGGUGGGGCUGCGCUCCACACUGCAGGGCCGCGGGGAGAUGGUGGAGCAGCUACGGGAGCUGACACGGCUGCUGGAGGCCAAGGACUUCCGGUCCCGGAUGGAAGGCGUGGGGCAGCUCCUGGAGCUCUGCAAGGCCAAGACGGAGCUUGUCACUGCCCACCUGGUCCAGGUCUUUGAUGCUUUCACCCCAAGGCUUCAGGAUUCCAACAAGAAAGUGAACCAGUGGGCGCUGGAGUCCUUCGCCAAGAUGAUCCCCCUCCUCAGAGAGAGCUUACACCCCAUGCUGCUCUCCAUCAUCAUCACUGUUGCAGACAACCUCAACUCCAAGAACUCAGGGAUUUACGCUGCUGCCGUGGCUGUGCUGGAUGCGAUGGUUGAGAGCCUGGACAACCUUUGCCUUCUACCAGCGCUUGCUGGGCGAGUGCGUUUCCUGAGUGGCCGUGCGGUGCUGGAUGUCACAGAUCGCCUGGCAGGAGGAUGUAGAUUCCACUUGGUGGAGAAAAGGAGAAUGGAGCUCAGAAAAGUGAAAUGCACAAGGUCUCUUGGUGAGGAGCCCAGGAUGUGUCCUGGGAGCCUGGCUGAAGGGCCAAGACCCCAACCCUGUGCUGUGCUGCUUCCCCCUGGCACUCUGCCUCCUGGGUGCCUGCAUGCAGUGGCCGGUCUCUCAACUUCUUGCUCUGCCCACUUGUGGCUGCCCUGCCCGGAAAGCCUUCUCCAUUCUUCUUCCUCUACCUGGGGGAUGCCUGCUUGGCUCUGGCAUUACCUUCUCCCUGUGUGCUUCUCAAGACUGCAUCCCACAUGGUAUCACUGGUCUGUCUACUGCCCUCCCCUCCUAGCCCAGCUGUGAGCAUCCAGAGAGGGGCCUGGCACAUGCUGCAUGGCUGAGGACCUUGGCACCAGCUGCCCUUUCAGCUUCUCCCCUGCCCCAUCUCUUGCGCCUGGCCUUGCCUCUAUGCAGGUUCUGUCCUUCCAGCAUUCCUGGAGUGGCCUCUUACCUUACGGGAAGGCAGGUGCGAGUGAGGCAGGGCUGGCUGCAGGUGAGCUGGGGGAGAACAGGGUAUGUAAGUAAGAUGGUCCUAGACACCAGACAAGGAACCCUUUGCCAUUGCUCAAAGUCAGCAUUUUCUGCAUGAAAGGUUUACCUGUCCUUGUCUGGGUAAUUUACGGGGCCCAGAGGUGGGCAAGUAUCUUCACCUUAUCCACUUACUGUAAUUUUUUCUUGUCUAUUUCCAAGAGACCUCAAAAGAAGAGCUUCUCCAUAGGUCUUCUGUUAACUCUGUGUCCACCAGGAACACAGAAGAAAAUUUUUAUUGACACAGGCGAGGCCUAAUAAUAGCACAGCUUAAUAGGAGUAAAUCUUCUGCUAAUUACUUCAGCUGCUUCUAAGCUUGAGUUUAAUGGGGCUUGCUCCCGCAUGCUGGCCCCCAGAAGGGCCUCACCAUCUUUGCCAGCUUAAGAGUCAACACCUGCCAGCCAGGCGACUGCCACAUCCUUGCACCUGGGGAAUGUGGCUCUGAAGUAGCCUGAGUUCUAUUAGCCAAGACGUGAUCAGAGAAGGUGGCCUGGGCUGUGGAAUUGAGUUUGGGUGGGGACUGCUACUCUUCCUGUGGAGUGAGCUUCCUGGGGGCUGAAGUGUAAACACGCCUCACUCUGUGGAAGAGA